AGCCCCGGCGACCCGGGCUUCUGUGAAACAUGGCGGUAGGCUGGGACCAUAACACAAGGUAAAAUACUGAAACACCGCUGGGUGCUGUUCCCUCGGUUGUUCCAGGGCUGUUUAGGGCGUAAAUGCAAUUGAGGGAACUGGGAGCCUGUCAUGGGCUUGGCUUCCUGUCUUCAUUGAUCUCUAGAGAGCCGGUCGGACGGAGAAGCCGCUCCACCUCCCACGGGGGCGUUACUGGCAGGACCCUAGGCAACGAUGCUACUGGGAGCUUCCCUUUGCCAGGUCCGGGUGCUUGUGUGCUAUCCUGCAACUCGAAGGAGUUCAGGUGCUUCCUCGAUCGCACCUGAUUCUGACCCUUUGCUUGUCACAGUGCCCGGUUCCCAGGUGGUUUCUCCAGUCCGCAGGCGAGUAGGAUCCCAAUCGGUCGAGUCCCAGUCCUCCCGGAUGUCAGACUCCCUACCCCCAUUCAGACAAAUGCCACAUUCGUGGCAGCACGUUGCCCUCUGUCUCUUUAAGAGUCUUGGCCUUGCCCGGAAGGAGUUUCGCACAGUGCUUCGGAAAAUGAGAAGGGGGCGGGGGAGGGCGAGAUGCUGAGAGACAGGUUCGACUGUCACUACUUUUCCUCGGCGCAGGAAACCUUCCGAAGGCAACGUGUCAACUCGUGGUGGAGAAUAGCCUUGUUUAUCUGUAGUAUAUAGAGUUGACAGCAUGACUAUAUGAAGGAAGAGGAAGGUUUUCCUGAAGAUGAGGCGACUGAAUCGGAAAAAAACUUUAAGUUUGGUAAAAGAGUUGGAUGCCUUUCCGAAGGUUCCUGAGAGCUAUGUAGAGACUUCAGCCAGUGGAGGUACAGUUUCUCUAAUAGCAUUUACAACUAUGGCUUUAUUAACCAUAAUGGAAUUCUCAGUAUAUCAAGAUACAUGGAUGAAGUAUGAAUACGAAGUAGACAAGGAUUUUUCUAGCAAAUUAAGAAUUAAUAUAGAUAUUACUGUUGCCAUGAAGUGUCAAUAUGUUGGAGCGGAUGUAUUGGAUUUAGCAGAAACAAUGGUUGCAUCUGCAGAUGGUUUAGUUUAUGAACCAACAGUAUUUGAUCUUUCACCACAGCAGAAAGAGUGGCAGAGGAUGCUGCAGCUGAUUCAGAGUAGGCUACAAGAAGAGCAUUCACUUCAAGAUGUGAUAUUUAAAAGUGCUUUUAAAAGUACAUCAACAGCUCUUCCACCAAGAGAAGAUGAUUCAUCACAGUCUCCAAAUGCAUGCAGAAUUCAUGGCCAUCUAUAUGUCAAUAAAGUAGCAGGGAAUUUUCACAUAACAGUGGGCAAGGCAAUUCCACAUCCUCGUGGUCAUGCACAUUUGGCAGCACUUGUCAACCAUGAAUCUUACAAUUUUUCUCAUAGAAUAGAUCAUUUGUCUUUUGGAGAGCUUGUUCCAGCAAUUAUUAAUCCUUUAGAUGGAACUGAAAAAAUUGCUAUAGAUCACAACCAGAUGUUCCAAUAUUUUAUUACAGUUGUGCCAACAAAACUACAUACAUAUAAAAUAUCAGCAGACACCCAUCAGUUUUCUGUGACAGAAAGGGAACGUAUCAUUAACCAUGCUGCAGGCAGCCAUGGAGUCUCUGGGAUAUUUAUGAAAUAUGAUCUCAGUUCUCUUAUGGUGACAGUUACUGAGGAGCACAUGCCAUUCUGGCAGUUUUUUGUAAGACUCUGUGGUAUUGUUGGAGGAAUCUUUUCAACAACAGGCAUGUUACAUGGAAUUGGAAAAUUUAUAGUUGAAAUAAUUUGCUGUCGUUUCAGACUUGGAUCCUAUAAACCUGUCAAUUCUGUUCCUUUUGAGGAUGGCCACACAGACAACCACUUACCUCUUUUAGAAAAUAAUACACAUUAACACCUCCCGAUUGAAGGAGAAAAACUUUUUGCCUGAGACAUAAAACCUUUUUUUAAUAAUAAAAUAUUGUGCAAUAUAUUCAAAGAAAAGAAAACACAAAUAAGCAGAAAACAUACUUAUUUUAAAAAAGAAAAAAAAGGAUAAAAAAACCCAAACUGAAAUUCUAUAUACGUUGUGUCUGUUACAAAUGUCGUAGAAGAAAUCAUGCAGCUAAACGAUGAAGAAGCCCAACUGGAGUGUUGCUUUGAAGAUGACGCCUUCUUAUAUUUUCAUAGCAAAUGGGUGGUAUCAAAAUCAGACAUUGCUUCUUGCUGAUAAAAAGCCUGAAGGAAAUAAGUGAAACUACAUCUAUGGGAAAAAAAAAAACAUUGAGAAGUGCAAAUGUUCGCAUCCUUUUGUUUUUAAAAGAUAUGAUGUCAGAAUAAAAUGUGGAAAACAUACGGAAAACUAGUCUAGACUUUAAAGAAUUGUGAUCAGGUCACAUUGUUAAUAAAAAAAAAAAACGGGCUAGUCCCUAUGUUAUAGCCAUAUUAAUGUUAAGCCAUAUUGACAAGACCAGUUAUCCAAUAAUUUGGUCUUAAAAAGUAACUACUUUUCUUUGAACUCUGGUUAUUGACUUAUCUAACUGUUGAAGAUAGAGUCUUAGAAGACUAAGGUAAAUUCUCACAGGGGCAGAUAUGUAGGUGUUAUGUAACUAGGGUGUCAUUCACAAAUGGUAUAGUAGAAUCUUAUACACGGAAAAGAAAGCACAUUUUUUUAAAAAAGAUGCCAAGUUUUUUAAUCUAAUCAUUAUAUUAUUGGUGUAUUUUGGGCAACAUAGGGUGAGUUAUAAAAAGAUCCGCUACUGAUAGUGAAAAUUACCGGUUUGUAAAACAUUAAGAGAAAAAAUAGGAUAUUUUAUACAUGUGGUGAGUGGAGAACAGGGUAACUUUAAAUGAAAGUGUAAGGCAAAUUGUAAGCACCACAAGAUAUAUCAGAUUUGAGAGGUGCCAUGUUAAACAUUGUCCAUUAAACUAUAAAACUGUAUUAUGAAGUAUUUGCAUUCAGGGUGUCCUGAAUAUGAUUGAUUCUGUAUUAGAUUGUGUUCUAACUUUCUUACUAUUUAAGGAUUGGUUCUAAAUCUUCACAUUAUAAAAGAUUAAAAACAGUGAGAGGGAGCUAUCACACAGGUACUAUUAAAAGCUGUAUUUGGAAUAUGUGUACCAAUAUCAGUUUUCCUUUUGUAGUACUGAAUGGCAGUAGAAGAAUCAGCAGCCAAUCCUCAAAGUUUAAAUCAUUUAAGGAAAUGGGGAAACAAAAUUCCAGGUAAAUAACAAGACUGAAAAACUAGAUUUAAAAUAGUGGUUUUAGAAAACAGGAUAUCACAAGUAACAGUUUUUCAAAUGGAUUUUUUUAAAGAUAAAUUUAUGAAAACAGGAUAAACAAUAUAAUGGAGAGAAGGAGAAAUAGUGAUGGGUCUGUUUUGCAGUAAAGUUUAUGCAGAAUGACGUUUUGCAGAAAAUAACAGAAGCAUCACUUUAAAAAAUAUAUCAUUAAGAGCCAUGACGUUAACUGAUGAAAAUAAGUGAUAUAACAUACUUUGAAAGAUUUUUAAACAGAAAAUUCUGAAUCGUGAAUGAGCCUUCUCUAGGUUUUAAUUUUUUUUCUUCAAAUUAUUUCCAACAAAGUUUGGCUAUAAACUAACACCAUCUAUCCACAGGAAUUUUAAUAGGAAAGGAUUAGAAUUGUAGACUGAUUGUUGGUCCUUUAAGUAUGCUUGGAAGAAAAUUCAAUCGAGUUUCAAGGCUUUUUCUAAAUGGGAGGGAGAACAAUAUUGAUUUAGGAUUAUUUUCUUUCAUUUAGGAUUAGAACAGUUAAGUGCCUUUAAAAAGGACUUUAAAAAUUAUUUUGAUACUUAUAUAUGAUUUUUAAUUGUUUUCGUAUUUUCCAAAUACCAUAUUAAAAUUUUAAUGAAAUUUAUCUCCUAUGAAAGGAAUUUCUUUAAAGCAAAAUUCUGCUUUGCCUUUGAUUUCCAUUUUAAAAGUUAAAGGCUUCCAUCUGAAACUCCUCAAAUAGAGUCAGAUUUUUGGCAAUGGAAGUAUUAAAAUUCCGAUCAGCCCUUUGGACGAUGAAGUUUACCUGCAUAUUAGGAUUUGUUAGGAGUUUUUGGCCUCACCAAGUGAUUCUUUUCUAUUGCAGAGAGCACUUUACUCACCUACCUGUUAUGCAACUUUCCCUAUGCCUGGAGGUGCCUCCAGCCAGGAUACCCUACUUUGUUACCCAAUUCUCCUUUUUGUUUUACAAGAGUAUUCAUAAUAUCUAUAUGUUUAUAUUCCAGACUACAUAUUUAAAAAUGAGAUCUCAAAUUAUAUGAAAUGGAUUUUUAAAUACUGUGUUUGCAUACAUUGACCUAUAAAGAAGAUUAAAUAUUUAGGUGAAUAAUUCCCUGCUGCAGUAUUUGUACACUUCAGACUACCUCUUAGGAAAAGCUUAACUUAGUAUUGCAAAAUUCCCUUUCUCUUUUUUUUUUUAAGAGAUGGGGUCUCGCACUGUUGCCCAGGCUGAAGUGCAGUGGCAUGAUUGUAACUCACUGCAUCCUCGAACUCCUGGGUUCAAGCAAUCCUCCUGCUUCCAUCUGCUGAGUAGGUAGGACUACAGCCAUGCACCAACAAACCUGGCUAAUUCUUUUUCAUUUAUAUAGUUAGUAUCUUGCUGUGUUGUUCAAGCUGGACUCCAACUCCCGGACUCAAGUAAUCCUCCCACCUUAGUCUCCUGCAUUGCUGGAAUUAUAGGCACGAGCCACUGCACCUGGCACCCAAAUUACUUCUAGUUCUCAAGUUAGAUGAUUAAUAUCACACUUUUCUCAUGUAUGUUUUAUGAUAGCAUUGAAUUUUUAUAAUUAAAAAUUUACUAAUGCAAACAAGAUUUACAGUCUUUAAUACAAUCUUAAUUUUGGAAUUCAUGAAGGAAUGACUAAGUUCUAAUUUUUUUUUUUUUUUUUUUGAAACUGAGUCUCGCUCUGUCGCCUAGGCUGGAGUGCAGUGGUGCAAUCUCAGCUCACUGCAACCUCCGUCUCCCGGGUUCAAGUGAUUCUCCUGCCUCAGCCUGUUGAGUAGCUGGGACUACAGGUGCGUACCACCAAGCCCAGCUAAUUUUUUUAUAUUUUUAGUAGAGACGGGGUUUCACUGUGUUAGCCAGGAUGGUCUCAAUCUCCUGACCUCAUGAUCCGCCCACCUUGGCCUCCCAAAGUGUUGGGAUUACAGGCAUGAGCCACUGCCCCUGGACAGAUCUAAUUUUUUAAUAGUGUAAGAGAGAUACACUGUGCAUUCCAUCUAUGUCCUGAGUUAGUAAUUCAAGUACCAAAAAGUAAUUUAAUAUGAAACUCCUUGAAAAUUCAGAGCUUACACUUGAAUUCAAAAUGCCUAUUUUUGAUUGUUUAAAAGUUACUUAAACCUGAGCUUUAGGACCUUUAAAAUCUCAGCAUGCCUUUUAAGCUAGUACUUUUCCUGUUUUGAGCUCUAGCAAACCUUCAGCAAGCCAAGGUGGUAGCCCUUUUUCAACACAAUCAAAAUAGAGAGGUCACCAGUUGUUUACUACCUUAUGGUAAAAUGCCCGGAUCAAGAUCCAUGUAUCCCCCCCAUAUUGUGAUGAUGCAAUCAAAGCAUAGUUUUUUUCUACUUUCUGAAAUAUUACUGAUGAAAUCACUUUACAUUUAAGAGGAGAAAACAGACUGCCUUGGAUUUUUUUUUUGUCUUGAGAGAAAAAACAAAAUAUUUAGUAUUGCAAGCAUAAACAUUUGGACUCAAUAAAUGACAAAUUAUGAAA